AGUGCGUGCUGGCCCGGGGUGGCAGGAGCCGCAGAGGCUUGGGCUGCAGAAAAAGGAUCCUGUUUGCUGUGUAAUCCUGAGAAUGGACUGCAAGAGAGGAAAAACUGGGCGUCUGCUUGGGAAUCUAUUGUGGAAACCCAGGGUGUUUCCCGACCAGUCCCUGGGCGCCAACUAGAGUAUGGACUGACCAGGUACCUGGAUGGAGACCUGAGCUGGAGAAGGAGAUGCGCUUGGGAGGAAAUUGCAGAGGCCGUCAACAUGGAAAAGCAGCCCCAGAACAGCAGGAGAGGCCUCGCCCCCCGAGAGGUGCCGCCAGCUGUUGGGCUGCUGCUGAUCAUGGCCCUGAUGAAUACUCUGCUCUACCUCUGCCUCGACCACUUCUUCAUCGCUCCUCGACAAUCCACUGUGGACCCCACACACUGUCCCUAUGGUCACUUCAGGAUAGGACAGAUGAAAAACUGCUCACCUUGGCUGUCCUGCGAGGAGCUGAGAACAGAAGUGAGACAGCUGAAGCGUGUUGGGGAAGGAGCUGUAAAGAGAGUCUUUCUGUCUGAGUGGAAGGAGCACAAAGUUGCACUCUCACAGCUCACCAGCCUGGAGAUGAAAGAUGAUUUCCUCCAUGGACUGCAGAUGCUGAAAUCUCUCCAAGGCACACAUGUUGUCACGCUGCUUGGCUAUUGUGAGGAUGACAACACUAUGCUUACUGAAUAUCACCCUCUAGGUUCCUUGAGUAACCUGGAAGAAACACUAAACCUUUCAAAGUACCAAAAUGUGAACACGUGGCAGCACAGGCUGGAGCUGGCCAUGGACUAUGUCAGCAUCAUUAAUUACCUGCACCACAGCCCUGUGGGCACACGGGUCAUGUGCGACUCCAACGACCUGCCGAAGACACUGUCCCAGUAUCUGCUAACAAGCAACUUCAGCAUUUUGGCAAAUGACUUGGACGCCUUACCCCUGGUGAACCACAGCUCCGGGAUGCUGGUGAAGUGCGGCCACAGGGAGCUGCAUGGGGAUUUCGUGGCUCCAGAGCAACUGUGGCCCUAUGGAGAGGACGUGCCUUUCCACGAUGAUCUCAUGCCCUCAUAUGAUGAGAAGAUUGACAUUUGGAAGAUCCCAGACAUCUCCAGUUUCCUUCUGGGGCACAUUGAAGGGAGUGAUAUGGUCCGAUUCCAUUUGUUUGAUAUUCACAAAGCAUGCAAGAGCCAGACUCCCUCAGAAAGACCCACUGCCCAGGACGUUCUGGAGACCUACCAGAAGGUCUUGGAUACACUUAGAGAUGCCAUGAUGUCUCAGGCAAGAGAGAUGCUGUGAAAACCAGUCCAGCCAAUGAAGGUGGGAUUGAAGGGCUGAAUGGAAGUUACAGCAUUCUACUCUGAUGGUGGAGUUUUUUGCCUGAGUUUCGUGUUUUAUUGUUUUUUUUAUGGCUUAGCCAUGUGGUUCGUUGUCCACAUCCACAUGUACGUUUGUAUGUAGUCCACAUUGGUUGUUAGAUUUUUUUUUUUUUCUUUGAGAUGCGGUCUUGCUCUGUUGCUGAGGCUGGAGUGCAGUGAUGUGAUCUUGGCUCACUGCAGCCUCUGCCUCCCAGGUUCAAGCAAUUCUCCCACCUCAGCCUCCUGAGUAGCUGGGAUUACAGGCACACCACCACGCCUGGCUAAUUUUUGUAUUUUUAGUGGAGGUGGGGUUUCACCAUGUUGGCCAGGCUGGUCCCGAACUCCUGACUUCCUCGGCCUCCCAAAGUGUUGGGAUUACAGGCAUGGGCCACUAUGCCUGGCCAGUUGUUAGAUUUCCAUGGAUUUGUAGUUUCCAAAGUUUCUCGUUAUUGAUUUCUACUUUUCUUCCAUUGUGGUCUGAGAAGGUACUUGAUAUGA